CUCUCCUCUCUCUCCUCCUCCUUCGCCGUCGCCGCCGCCGCCGGCCGCCCGCCGGCCGCCACGACCCCAGUCCCCGGCGGGCGGGCGGAGGAGGCGACCGCCGCGCGCUGCUGCACUCAUCCUGCCGCCGCCGCGAUGCGCAGAGGGGCCGAGCCGCCUGGGGGCCGCCGCCGCCGCCGCGCCGCACCAUGAAGCUCCGCAGCAAGGCGGCGGCGCUGCUCUUGCUCGCGCUGGCCGCGCUGCUGCUGGCGCUGCUGUCCCUGCGCGCUGGCCGCGCUGAGCCCCCAGCGCUGCCCGCGCGCCCCGCGUCCGCCCCGCAGCGCCACCCCGCGCCUGUCCCCGCGCGCUGGCCGGGGCCGGGCGCCCUCCCCGGGGCCAGCCCGGGAGUUCGGAGGCGCCGGCCCCCGCGUCCGCGCCCCCGAGCGGGCCGCCGGGGCGCUGCGAGACUGGAGAAGUUGGCGAGGAGGCCUGGAGAACCCAGGAGUUUCCAAGCUGUGCUGCCACCCGAGCUCUGGAUCCACCUGGCUGUGGUGGCCUGUGGCAAUCGGCUGGAGGAGACGCUGGUCAUGCUCAAAUCAGCUGUGCUUUUUAGCCACAGGAAGAUCCAAUUCCACAUCUUCACUGAAGACUCUCUGAAGCCCGAGUUUGAUAAGCAGUUACGCCAGUGGCCUGACUCAUAUACAAAGAAGUUUGAGCACAGAAUCUACCCCAUCACAUUUUCUGUUGGAAACCCUCAGGAGUGGAAGAAAUUGUUCAAACCCUGUGCUGCCCAGAGACUCUUUCUUCCGGUGAUUUUAAAGGAUGUGGACUCACUUCUCUACGUGGACACCGAUGUCCUCUUUCUGAGACCUGUUGAUGACAUCUGGAAGCUUCUGAGGCUGUUUAAUUCCACCCAGCUUGCAGCCAUGGCCCCUGAGCACGAAAUCCCCAAGAUUGGCUGGUACAGCCGCUUUGCUAGGCAUCCUUUCUAUGGCUCUGCAGGAGUUAAUUCAGGAGUCAUGUUAAUGAAUUUAACUCGGAUAAGAAGUACCCAGUUCAAGAACAGCAUGAUUCCAACAGGCCUGGCUUGGGAGGACAUGUUGUACCCUCUGUACCAGAAGUACAAGAAUGCCAUCACGUGGGGAGACCAGGAUUUAUUAAAUAUUAUUUUUUAUUUCAACCCAGAGUGUCUCUAUGUAUUCCCCUGCCAGUGGAACUACCGUCCCGAUCACUGCAUGUACGGAAGCAACUGCAGAGAGGCUGAGCAUGAAGGUGUGUCUGUUCUGCAUGGAAACCGAGGCGUCUACCAUGACGAUAAGCAACCAACGUUCAGAGCACUCUAUGAAGCAAUACGGGAUUUUCCCUUUCAAGACAAUCUCUUUCAAUCCAUGUAUUACCCCCUUCAGCUGAAGUUUUUGGAGACUGUGCACACUUUAUGUGGACGAAUCCCGCAAGUUUUUCUGAAGCAAAUUGAGAAAACAAUGAAAAGGGCUUAUGAGAAACACGUCAUCAUCCAUGUUGGCCCCAACCAGAUGCACUGAAUAUUUUGUCUUGUUGCAAGUCAAUUAGGUGUCUUGUGACCAAGGAAAUACUAAUCUCUAAGCUGCCUGGGUCUUUUUGUGUGAAUAUUUAAUGGUGCUCCAUGACUGUUGAGUUUUAAAAACCUCGUUAAAUUUUGCCAAAUCAGUUGCCCCCAAAAGGGAAUAUGCUUUUCCUUAUUUUUUUUUCUAAAAUGCUAUUUAUCUCUAAGGAAAAAAAAAAAAGACUAUUACUCAUUUAACAUUGUUUAAGCAGGUUGAGCUAGCUGUGAAAAUAGCUUUUGUGAGCCUUCUAAUUCCUAAACGUCUGAGACCAUUUCAGUGGCACCUGAGGUGUUAUAUUGAUCUAGCAUUCCUGAGACUCUUUCUAUGCAACUGACUCCCCCACACCCGUGUUAUAAAAGUAAUACACACUUUUGAAACAGAGAGACACACUUGUAGAGCAUAUGGGUCAAGGGCUCAACAUCAAGAUUAGAUUAGCCAUAAUCCUAUUGACCAGUGGAAAAGAUUGUUUCCAUUUUAAAGCAGUUCCUUACAACCUUUUUUCUCUACUUUUGCAUUUUCCACUCUAACACACAUCUAAAACAGGUAAUCUCAGUAAAAGCUGGCCUUUUUGCUGAGAUUUUUAUGUGGGAGACUAAAAUAUUAGAUGAGAUGAUUAUGUGUACAGAAUUUUAUUUAAAAUACAUCUGAGAGAAUCAUUCAGAUACUUGGGUAGUGUUAAAGGAUGAAGCAUGUAUCUGGGGGUAUUUCUUCUUUUUCUUUCUUUCUUUUUUUUUUUUUUUUUUUUUUUGAGACGGAAUCUCACUCUGUAGCCCAGGCUAGAAUGCAGUGGCAGGAUCUCGGCUCACUGCAGCUUCCACCUCCUGGGUUCAAGUGAUUCUCAUGCCUCAGCCUCCCCAGUAGCUGGGAUUACAAGUGUGUGCCACCACACCCGGCUAAUUUUUGUAUUUUUAGUAGAGACACGGUUUUACCAUGUUGGCCAGGCUGGUCUUGAUCUCCAGACCUCAAGUGAUCUGCCUGCCUCAGCCUCCCAAAGUGCUGGGAUUACAAGUGUGAGCCACUGCACUCAGCCAAUCUGGGAGUAUUUCUAAAGAAAAAAAUUACUUUGAUUUGUGGAGGACUAAAUCAUAAUACAUUUCUAUGCAACAAUAGCUUCUGAGAGGAAAUUCAGGAAUGUUUGUGUUUACCACAGACAAAAACAUUUGAUCUGUUAAUCAUCAGUAGCUGUGGUCAUCUCUCUUUCUUAAACUCUUGGGCAAUGGGUGGAAAUCAGAGACCAACUUCAAAUUUAAUGUGUAAAAAACAAAUAGUUCAGCUGCUUCUAUUGGUAAGAAAAUUCAACUUCCUACCAGCCUUAGAAAGGUCUCUUUAAACAAUUUCUUUCCCCCUAGGGUUACCUAGCUGGUCCAUACAGGUUUUAUCACCUCACUGCAAGGAGGAAGUUGAAUAUUCUGUUCCCCACGGGGAUCUGGCUUAAUCCCUAGUUGCUCAUAUAGUUGGUAUCAGCAUAGCAAUAUUUUGCAUAAUGCUUUAUUUUUCUCAAAUGACUAUUGCAUAGAUGAUCUUGAUAUUUGCAACAGCCUAGUGGAUUUGGUAGGGUCCUGAAUCAUCUCUAUAAGGCAAACAAGGAAAUUGUAACACAAAGAAAUAAACAUAUUGAAUAUAAUUGCUAUUCUGUAAGACAUACAGUCUGUGUAAGAUGUAUCUUAUUUACAGAGACAUUUUUGAAAAUUAAAAUAUUAAAUACUUUUUGUUA